ACCUUUUCCGGCGCGGGCCAGCGGCUUCCGGGAGGGGGCCCGGCUGCGGGCGGCAGUCCGGCAGUGGCGGGGCCCGGGGGGCGCCCAAGAUGGCGGCGGGCGGCGCGGAGGGCGGCUCGGGCCCCGGCGCCGCCAUGGGGGACUGCGCGGAGAUUAAGUCGCAAUUCCGCACGCGCGAGGGUUUCUACAAGCUACUCCCGGGCGACGGCGCCGCUCGCAGGUCGGGUCCGGCUUCCGCCCAGACUCCGGUGCCGCCUCAGCCACCGCAGCCCCCGCCCGGCCCUGCCUCCGCCUCCGGUCCCGGCGCUGCAGGCCCCGCGUCGUCCCCGCCGCCCGCAGGCCCCGGACCCGGGCCCGCCCUGCCCGCCGUGCGCCUCAGCCUCGUGCGCCUCGGGGAGCCGGACAGCGCCGGGGCCGGGGAGCCGCCCGCCACGCCCGCGGGGCUGGGCUCGGGGGGAGACCGCGUCUGCUUCAACUUGGGCCGUGAGCUCUAUUUCUACCCAGGCUGCUGUCGUCGUGGGAGCCAACGGUCCAUUGACCUCAACAAGCCAAUUGACAAGCGGAUCUACAAGGGCACCCAGCCCACCUGCCACGAUUUCAACCAGUUCACUGCUGCCACCGAGACCAUCUCGCUGCUGGUGGGCUUCUCAGCGGGUCAAGUGCAGUACCUGGAUCUCAUCAAAAAGGACACCAGCAAGCUGUUCAAUGAGGAGCGGUUGAUCGACAAGACCAAGGUGACAUAUCUGAAGUGGCUGCCUGAGUCGGAGAGCCUGUUCCUGGCAUCACACGCCAGUGGCCACCUGUACCUGUACAACGUCAGCCACCCCUGCGCCUCGGCCCCGCCCCAGUACAGCCUGCUGAAGCAGGGCGAGGGCUUCUCUGUCUAUGCUGCCAAGAGCAAGGCACCCCGCAACCCGCUGGCCAAGUGGGCGGUGGGUGAGGGGCCCCUCAACGAGUUCGCCUUCUCGCCCGAUGGCCGGCACCUGGCCUGUGUGAGCCAGGAUGGCUGCCUGCGCGUCUUCCACUUCGACUCCAUGCUCCUGCGUGGGCUCAUGAAGAGCUACUUUGGGGGCCUGCUGUGUGUGUGCUGGAGCCCUGACGGCCGCUACGUGGUGACGGGUGGCGAAGAUGACCUGGUCACCGUGUGGUCCUUCACCGAGGGCCGCGUGGUGGCUCGAGGCCAUGGCCACAAGUCCUGGGUCAACGCUGUGGCCUUUGACCCCUACACCACAAGGGCAGAGGAGGCGGCGACAGCAGCCGGUGCUGAUGGGGAGCGGAGCGGCGAAGAGGAGGAGGAGGAGCCCGAGGCUGCGGGCACAGGCUCGGCCGGGGGCGCCCCGCUCUCUCCACUGCCCAAGGCUGGCUCCAUUACUUACCGCUUUGGCUCGGCGGGCCAGGACACGCAGUUCUGCCUGUGGGACCUCACUGAAGACGUGCUCUACCCGCACCCCCCCCUGGCCCGCACCCGCACCCUCCCUGGCACACCUGGCACCACGCCACCGGCCGCCAGCAGCUCGAGGGGUGGCGAGCCUGGCCCAGGCCCCCUGCCUCGCUCGCUGUCCCGCUCCAACAGUCUCCCGCACCCAGCUGGCGGGGGCAAGGCGGGCGGCCCGGGUGUGGCGGCAGAGCCUGGCACACCAUUCAGCAUUGGCCGCUUCGCCACGCUCACACUGCAGGAGCGGCGGGACCGGGGGGCAGAGAAGGAGCACAAGCGCUACCACAGCCUGGGCAACAUCAGCCGGGGUGGCAGUGGCGGCAGUGGCAGUGGUGGGGAGAAGCCCAGCGGCCCUGUUCCCCGCAGCCGCCUGGACCCCGCCAAGGUGCUGGGCACUGCGCUGUGCCCGCGCAUCCACGAGGUGCCCCUGCUGGAGCCCCUUGUGUGCAAGAAGAUCGCCCAGGAGCGGCUCACAGUCCUCCUGUUCCUGGAGGACUGCAUCAUCACUGCCUGCCAGGAGGGCCUCAUCUGCACCUGGGCCCGGCCGGGCAAGGCGUUCACAGACGAGGAGACCGAGGCCCAGACAGGGGAAGGAAGUUGGCCCAGGUCACCCAGCAAGUCAGUGGUAGAGGGCAUCUCCUCCCAACCAGGCAACUCCCCGAGUGGCACAGUGGUGUGAAGCCAUGGAUAUCGGGCCCCCCCAACCCCAUGCCCCCAGCCUCCUAGCCAUAACCCUCCCUGCUGACCUCACAGAUCAACGUAUUAACAAGACUAACCAUGAUGGAUGGACUGCUCCAGUCCCCCCACCUGCACAAAAUUUGGGGGCCCCCCAGACUGGCCCGGACACGGGCGAUGUAAUAGCCCUUGUGGCCUCAGCCUUGUCCCCCACCCACUGCCAAGUACAAUGACCUCUUCCUCUGAAACAUCAGUGUUACCCUCAUCCCUGUCCCCAGCAUGUGACUGGUCACUCCUGGGGAGAGACUCCCCGCCCCUGCCACAAGAGCCCCAGGUCUGCAGUGUGCCCCUCAGUUGAGUGGGCAGGGCCGGGGGUGGUCCAGCCCUCGCCCGGCCCCCACCCCAGCUGCCCUUGCUAUUGUCUGUGCUUUUGAAGAGUGUUAAAUUAUGGAAGCCCCUCAGGUUCCUCCCUGUCCCGCAGGACCUCUUAUUUAUACUAAAGUUCCCUGUUUUCUCAGCGGGUCUGUCCCCUUCGGAGGAGAUGAUGUAGAGGACCUGUGUGUGUACUCUGUGGUUCUAGGCAGUCCGCUUUCCCCAGAGGAGGAGUGCAGGCCUGCUCCCAGCCCAGCGCCUCCCACCCCUUUUCAUAGCAGGAAAAGCCGGAGCCCAGGGAGGGAACGGACCUGCGAGUCACACAACUGGUGACCCACACCAGCGGCUGGAGCAGGACCCUCUUGGGGAGAAGAGCAUCCUGCCCGCAGCCAGGGCCCCUCAUCAAAGUCCUCGGUGUUUUUUAAAUUAUCAGAACUGCCCAGGACCACGUUUCCCAGGCCCUGCCCAGCUGGGACUCCUCGGUCCUUGCCUCCUAGUUUCUCAGGCCUGGCCCUCUCAAGGCCCAGGCACCCCAGGCCGGUUGGAGGCCCCGACUUCCACUCUGGAGAACCGUCCACCCUGGAAAGAAGAGCUCAGAUUCCUCUUGGCUCUCGGAGCCGCAGGGAGUGUGUCUUCCCGCGCCACCCUCCACCCCCCGAAAUGUUUCUGUUUCUAAUCCCAGCCUGGGCAGGAAUGUGGCUCCCCGGCCAGGGGCCAAGGAGCUAUUUUGGGGUCUCGUUUGCCCAGGGAGGGCUUGGCUCCACCACUUUCCUCCCCCAGCCUUUGGGCAGCAGGUCACCCCUGUUCAGGCUCUGAGGGUGCCCCCUCCUGGUCCUGUCCUCACCACCCCUUCCCCACCUCCUGGGAAAAAAAAAAAAAAAAAAAAAAAAAGCUGGUAUAAAGCAGAGAGCCUGAGGGCUAAAUUUAA